AUUCACGGAGCCGGCCGGCCUCCCGCCCUGGGUGUUUCCCUGCCUUGUAGCCAGGGUGCCAGCCUGGGAAGUAGUUUCGUUUCCUUCUGCCUCCGGGAUUAGUUUCCAGGCACCCUCUCAGGCGCCCGAGGCCCGGGAAGGGGGCGAAGAAGGAGGGAGACUUGUCUAGGGGCUGCCCGGCCCGGCAGAGCGGGGUUGAUGGACCGGGCCGCCCGGUGCAGCGGCGCCAGCUCCCUGCCACUGCUCCUGGCCCUUGCCCUGGGUCUAGUGAUCCUUCACUGUGUGGUGGCAGAUGGGAAUUCCACCAGAAGUCCUGAAACUAAUGGCCUCCUCUGUGGAGACCCUGAGGAAAACUGUGCAGCUACCACCACACAAUCAAAGCGGAAAGGCCACUUCUCUAGGUGCCCCAAGCAAUACAAGCAUUACUGCAUCAAAGGGAGAUGCCGCUUCGUGGUGGCCGAGCAGACGCCCUCCUGUGUCUGUGAUGAAGGCUACAUUGGAGCAAGGUGUGAGAGAGUUGACUUGUUUUACCUAAGAGGAGACAGAGGACAGAUUCUGGUGAUUUGUUUGAUAGCAGUUAUGGUAGUUUUUAUUAUUUUGGUCAUCGGUGUCUGCACAUGCUGUCACCCUCUUCGGAAACGUCGUAAAAGAAAGAAGAAAGAAGAAGAAAUGGAAACUCUGGGUAAAGAUAUAACUCCUAUCAAUGAAGAUAUUGAAGAGACAAAUAUUGCUUAAACAGGUGCCUCCUACUAGCUAAACCCACCAGAAACCAGAGGGCAAUGGAGCCCUGGUGAUGGAAUCUGAAGUGGCCAGUCUCCUGGAGACAGAGCAGGGCAGAGAAAGGCUCCAAGAAGGCACAUGACGCGUAACUAGCACAACAAAGCAGGAUAGUUUUGGUUGUAAUAACAUAAAAUCCAACUCAAACUGGCUUAAAAUGAAGGCAACGUAUUGGCUCACAUGAAUGGCAGUCCAGAGGUAAGGUGGGCUUCACACUUGUCAAACCAGAGGCUCACACGUAAGGAACCAGAUUAUUUCCCUCUUUCUGCUCACUAUUCUGAGUUGGCUUUCAUCCUUGGUCAGUUCCUCUUAGGUCCUAAGAAAGGCCAGUAGCAAUUAGGGCUACAAGCUUCCUCGUUUACAUCCAGUAUGAGAGAGUAGUGUCUUUCCACAGCUCAGUUGUACAAAGAAUCUCUUCCAGAAAAUCCCAGCAGCUUAAUGGGGUUGGUAAAUGCUUGACGAGAAAUUAUAUGUGCUCCUAACUUAUUACAAAAACAACAUUAUUGAAUUGAAAACAAAAUGGCUGGCUCUGGAUUUUUAAAUUAUUAUUAUUAUUGCAUAGUCCAUUUCUUUUAAGUGAUGUGCUGUUAUUUUCUUCAUUCUCAGAGGCUAUGAAGUUACCUCCAGGUUGGUGGCAAGCUGCAAAGUGCCUUGCUCAUUUGAAAAUGGACAGAAUGUGUCUCAGGAAAACAGCUAGUAGACAUGAAUUUUAAAUAAUGUAUUUACUUUUUAUUUGCAACUUUAGUUUGUGUUAUUAUUUUUUAAUAAGAACAUUAAUUAUAUGUAUAUUGUCUAGUAAUUGGGAAAAAAGCAACUGGUUAGGUAGCAACAACAGAAGGGAAAUUUCAAUAACCUUUCACUUAAGUAUUGUCACCAGGAUUACUAGUCAAACAAAAAAGAAAAGUAGAAAGGAGGUUAGGUCUUAGGAAUUGAAUUAAUAAUAAAGCUACCAUUUAUCAAGCAUUUACCAUGUGCUAAUAAGUUUGAAAUAUAUUAUUUCCUUUAUUCCUUUCAGCAAUCCAUGAGAUAGCUAUUAUAAUCCUCAUUUCCUACAUAUGGAAACAGGGCCAAAGAAGUCAAGUCAAAUAAUCUAAUCCAGAUUUAGAGAGUUGGAGAUUGGUAGAGACAGACUAGAAAUCAAGAUUUAUCUAAAUCAAAAUCUAUGCUCUUAACCAUCAUUUUUGUUAGUCUGAAUCGGUGCAACCUAACUCAAUAAUAUAACCCAAGGUUUUAUACUGAACUGUGUUUUGGUAUGAUUGUGAGAUGUCAAGACCGUCUUCCCACAGGCACACAGAAUGAGAAAUCCUGGCCUAUAUUGCUGUUACCAUCAUGCUUUCUAUAGAAUUGGCUUUUAUUAUGUUUCUUUGCUCCUUUAUAAAUUCUCAAUGAUGUGACUACAUUUUUACAUUAUUAAAGCAAAUAGAUUGGCCCCAUAACUAGGGAAAUGAAUAGAGAUGGAAAAGUAAAUGCUUGGCAUUCCUUAAGCCCUGGGUAAGUGUUUAUGCUCAAUAAAAUAUAAAUAAUAUUACUGAAAGAGGCUGUUUAUAUGGGAGUAAUGGUCAGUGACAACACUGGAGAGACCAGGUAGGGACCGGUUGUGACCAUAUCCUCAUUUAUGUUCUUGAUGACAGCAUAUAUGAUUGCUCUCAGGUAAAUUUUGAUGCAGUAAAUUCAUGACCAUAACAUCUAUUACUUGGGACCAUCUUGCCAAGUGCUCCUUUACUCCAUGAAAUAUUUAAUAAACACUGCUUUAAACCUGGAAAAGCACAAUCUACAUUUAGUGAAUAUUUCAUAGAAUAUUUAACUUUUUACAUUGAUUACGUGGUUCACUUACAAAAAUCGAUGGAAGAUGCCCCCCAACUUGUGCCUGUCGGCCAAGCAGCUUCUUUUUUAGAAUCUUUGCAAAUUUUACUUUGCAAUGUAGAUUCCAUAGUGAAGUGGAGAAUUCAGACAAAUGCUGAAAUCGCAUAUUACCUUCUAGCAUCCAUGGUGUUUUGAGUGAAGCUGGGGCUGUACUUACAUAUGAUACAUAAAUAGCUCCCCUAUUAGUAAAAGCUAAGCCAAACAACUGAUAAUUUUCAAAAUCUAUUUUUUCUCCUGAUUUAAUGGUCAUACUUGAAACACAAUUAUAUCCAACUGAUCCAUGUUGUAUAUGCCUUAUUUUCAAAAGUCUCAUUUAAGCUCAUUCAUGCCCUUUCUCUUAUGUAGUCUUCUUCGAUACGAAAGGAGCUUGGAAUAAAUAUCCAUUAGAGCUUUUAAAAACACAAAACAAUGCUUUAAUGUUUCUUUUUUCCUGGACUGAGUUUGGCUGACCAACAAAAUCUCUCAAGCCAUUUUGUUUUGAUCCUAAAAUAUCAAUGGUGGCUCUCGAAAUUUGGUAGAUCUGAUAUCAAGAAAGAAUUUCAAAGAUUUUUAUAUCUUUUCAAAAUGUAUUUUAUAGUUGCUUUGCAUACACUAAAUAACUUUGUUUAUGUAAACUGUCAAUAUUAUCAUGUAAUAAAAUAAAUUUAUUUUUAAAACAAA